AUAUCACCUGAGAGAGUUCCCAAGUCUACAAUUGCUCUACUAGUUACUAUUCAGUGUUUGUGAAAAAUUUUAAUCUCAGUACUGUGAAGAAGCUGGAAAAAGGGAUAUUAUGGGGCUAAAAGCUCUCUGUUUGGGGCUGCUUUGUGUUCUUUUUGUCUCUCAUUUUUACACACCCAUGCCAGACAACAUUGAAGAAAGCUGGAAAAUAAUGGCCUUGGAUGCCAUCGCUAAAACUUGUACAUUUACGGCUAUGUGUUUUGAAAAUAUGCGUAUUAUGAGAUAUGAAGAGUUUAUAUCCAUGAUAUUCAGGCUGGAUUAUACCCAACCACUUUCAGAUGAAUACAUCACAGUGACUGAUACAACAUUUGUUGACAUUCCAGUACGAUUGUACUUGCCAAAAAGAAAGUCAGAAACCCGAAGGCGAGCUGUGAUAUAUUUUCAUGGUGGUGGUUUUUGUUUUGGAAGUUCCAAACAGAGGGCUUUUGACUUCCUGAAUAGAUGGACGGCAAACACGCUUGAUGCUGUUGUUGUAGGCGUGGACUAUAGGCUGGCUCCUCAACACCACUUUCCUGCUCAGUUUGAAGAUGGCCUUGCUGCAGUCAAAUUUUUUCUUUUGGAAAAAAUUCUUACAAAAUAUGGAGUGGAUCCCACCCGAAUCUGCAUUGCGGGAGACAGUUCUGGGGGCAAUUUAGCAACAGCGGUCACUCAACAGGUGCAGAAUGAUGCUGAAAUAAAACAUAAAAUCAAGAUGCAAGUCUUACUUUACCCUGGCUUACAGAUAACAGAUUCUUAUUUGCCAUCUCACCGAGAAAAUGAGCAUGGUAUAGUUUUGACCAGGGAUGUAGCCAUAAAACUCGUGAGCUUAUAUUUCACCAAGGAUGAAGCACUUCCCUGGGCAAUGAGAAGAAACCAACACAUGCCUCUGGAGUCAAGACAUCUGUUUAAGUUUGUUAACUGGAGUAUUCUUCUUCCUGAGAAGUAUAGAAAAGACUAUGUAUAUACUGAACCAAUUCUUGGAGGACUUAGUUAUUCAUUGCCAGGACUUACAGACAGCAGAGCAUUACCCUUGUUGGCCAAUGAUUCUCAGUUACAGAAUUUGCCACUAACCUAUAUUCUUACUUGUCAACAUGAUCUCUUAAGAGAUGAUGGACUUAUGUAUGUUACAAGACUUCGAAAUGUUGGAGUCCAAGUUGUUCAUGAACAUAUUGAGGAUGGAAUUCAUGGAGCUUUAUCAUUCAUGACUUCACCAUUUUAUUUACGUCUAGGUCUUAGGAUAAGAGAUAUGUAUGUAAGUUGGCUGGAUAAGAAUUUAUAAAUAUGUGAUGUGUAUGUAUAGCCCUUACAUAGUGGAUUGUAAUUUGUGAUAUUUUGUGGUUUUGGAGCAAAGAACAAUGUCAUUUGAGUUAUCUAAAUCUACAUUUGCAACAUUUGUAGCAGUUAAUGUGUGUCCUUGAAGAGUUAUUAAAUUUUCUGACUUGCAGACCCUGAAUAUGUAAAAUGUAUGUAAUCCUGCCUAUUUUCUCCUUACUUAUAAUUUAUUAUAAUUAUGUUGGUUCUAAUAAGAACCAAUGCUUAUUAAAGUUGAGAAAUAAGAGUGGUUAUUGGCAAAUUAAGCAAGAUACUUUCCAGAUAGGCACAGAAAUUGUUGUAGUGAGUGGGAAGAGGAAAAAACAUGGAACAAACUUGCUGCUAAAAAUAUAUGGAAACCACUGGACUAAAUAAACCCUAAGGACCCUAUAUUAGUUUCCUGUGACUAUUGUAGCAAAUUACUACAAAUUCAGUCGCUUUAAACAACAGAUAUUUAUUCUUUUACAGUUCUGGGGUCCUAAAGCAUGAAAUUAGUAUUAACUAGGCCCAAACCAAGUCACAGGCAAGAGACAUGACUCCCUUGGAGACUCUCUAGAAGGUGCUCUUUGCCUCUUUUAACCUCUGGUGGCUGCCAGUAUUCUUUGACUAUUCUUAGAUCAGUUUAAUCUUGAAGGCCAGCAUCUUCCAAUCUCUUUCUGCUUCAUCUUCACAUUGCCUUCUUCUCUGCCUGUGUCUAAUCUCCCUAUGGGCUUCUCUUAGAAAAACACAUGUGUUUACAUUUAGGAGGGUCCACCUGAAUAGUCUAGGAUAAUCUCUGCAUCUCACGAUCCUCAAUUUAAUUGUAUUUGCAGAUUUCCCCACCCUUUUCUAUAUAAAGUAACCUUCAGAGAUUAGGAUGUAGUUAUCUUUUGGGAGGCCAUUUUUAAAAAUAUUUUUUAAAGGAGGCAGCAGAUCAAUAUUAUAAUUCAAGAAUCUGAUCUAAAUAUGCAUUCAAUAAUGAAGAACAUUUGAGUAUGGACUAGAAAAGCUUCUCCAAAAAACUUUCAAAUAUAUCAUCUCAAAUUACCUAAAGAAUAAAUCACUUCUGUAGCCCUUUUGUUGAGUGGAAUCAUAAACAAAAAACUGAAAAUUUAUUGCUAUGAAAACAGAUCCAUGGUACAAUGUUAUAAAUUUUGAGUAUUAAGCAUAGUCAGUUGAAUCCAACUAAGAAGUUAAAAAUGUAGUAAGAAAUGUGUAUAUGUAUGAGUAUGUGCAUGUGUGUGGGAAAAAUCUACCAUCCAAUUGACCCAAAAACAACUUACUCAGUUGGGACCAGACAUUUUUCUCAAUUCUCCAUGAUUCAGAAGGCAAUUAAGAAUUACAAUUUCAACAGUCCACAAACAAAAUAAGAUUUUUUUAAUGUAGAGAGAAAUUAAUUAUGUUCAAAGAGCCCUUUUUCUUUCACUCAAUUUCAGUACCCCAAAGCUAAAAACGCAAACAUGACUAUGACAAAUGAAAAUAAGUAUCAUGGGAAUCUGUUUUUUUCCUCUGAGAAAUAAAAUCUAAAUGGAGAUUUGAUACUAUAUGCUAUACUACAUACACUAAGAAUAUUGUAUUUUUCAUAAUUCUGAUUUAAUCUCCUGUAAACUUGAUAUAUUUUAAAAUUUGUAAUUUGUUUUUCAUGAUACUGAAUCUGGUUCCAGUUCUUUUUCAUCAUUUAAUAUACUGGCUACCCGUUCUAAUUAGGAAAACAAGUCCUAGAAAUCUCUUCAUUUUGACAGCAAGUGCUGAUUUGUAAGAAAAUCAUUAAAAAUGCAGCUCUCUAGGAAGCACAUUUUGUUGAUUGUCCUAUUGUCUGAACAUUUUCACAGUGAUUCCUGACUAAAAAUCCUUUUAAUUUUGUAAGCACUACACUAGUGUGUCAUGUCACUA